ACGGCCCGGCGCGUGGCUCGGGCUCGGGCGGAGCUGGAGACGUGUGGAGCUGUUCGAGGACUCGCGGGUGUGCAGGGAUGCGGUUUAAUAUUUUCAUGUGAUUCCUAAAAGAAUCUGAGGCUCAAGAAAAGAGGGCAUCUUAAUAUCCUGCACUUUCAGUCAUUGAGGGCAUGAUCACAAAGAUCAAAGCCAUUUUUAGGCAGUGCACCUAUGAUAUGUGUUUUAGAAAUAGCCGUUAAACUUUGGUUUGAAUGAAGAAUGUCUCUCAAUCCACCUAUAUUUCUCAAACGAAGUGAAGAAAAUAGUUCAAAAUUUGUGGAAACAAAACAGUCACAAACUACUUCCAUAGCUUCAGAAGAUCCCCUUCAAAACUUAUGUUUAGCAUCUCAAGAAGUUCUUCAAAAAGCUCAGCAAAGUGGGAGAUCAAAAUGUCUCAAAUGUGGUGGUUCCAGAAUGUUCUACUGCUAUACAUGUUAUGUUCCAGUUGAAAAUGUACCUAUUGAACAGAUUCCACUUGUGAAGCUUCCAUUGAAGAUUGACAUCAUUAAACAUCCAAAUGAAACAGAUGGCAAAAGUACUGCUAUACAUGCAAAACUCUUAGCACCUGAAUUUGUAAACAUUUACACGUAUCCGUGUAUUCCAGAAUAUGAAGAAAAGGACCAUGAAGUUGCACUCAUUUUUCCUGGACCUCAGUCUAUCUCAAUAAAAGAUAUUUCUUUUCAUCUGCAAAAAAGGAUUCAAAAUAAUGUUAGAGGCAAAAAUGAUGACCCUGACAAGCCAUCUUUUAAACGCAAAAGAACUGAAGAACAAGAGUUCUGUGAUUUGAAUGACAGCAAGUGCAAAGGCACAACACUGAAAAAAAUUAUAUUUAUAGAUAGCACCUGGAACCAAACAAACAAAAUAUUCACUGAUGAGCGACUUCAAGGGUUGUUACAAGUUGAGUUGAAAACAAGAAAAACUUGCUUUUGGCGCCAUCAAAAAGGAAAGCCAGAUACUUUCCUUUCUACAAUUGAAGCCAUUUACUACUUUCUGGUAGACUACCAUACUGAUAUAUUAAAAGAGAAAUACAGAGGGCAAUAUGACAAUCUUUUAUUUUUCUAUUCUUUUAUGUACCAGUUGAUAAAGAAUGCCAAAUGCUCUGGAGAUAAGGAAACAGGAAAACUUACACAUUAGUUUUUAACAAGCCACUUAUGUCUUUUUAUUUUGCUAACAUUAAUAAACUUAUAUUUGUGCUUUGUUUUUUCUUAAGAAAUAAUCAUAUAUAAUGCCUGUAAGACCAUUUGAAAAAAUUCCAGUUUCAUAUAUAUCACUUCAUAUUUCUUGAAGGAAAUUGUAUCUGGGGGAAUUUUUCAGAGAUACUGUUGAUUGAAAAACUUACUUCAGAAGUUAUUUGCUCAGUGAAACCUCAGUUUCAUUACUACAUUUUAAUAUAGUGUGUUAUGUCUCUGUGAUUAGAUAUAACAUAUUCCAUUAGAUCUAAUUAGCUAUUUAUUUCAACAUCUUUAUAUCUUUUCACCUGUACUCAUGACCACCUUUAGAAGUAAAUGGGGUUACAAUCUGCUGGCUGAAAAAUAGGUCAUAAGUGAUUUUUCUUGAGGUUAGUAGCAAACAUAGGCAGAACUAGAAUUAGAAUUCUGGUAUCUAGGGCUGUUUCUUUAAGUCCUAAGGUUGUUAAAAGCAGAGACUCUGGAGCUAGACUACCUGAAUCUAAAUCUCAGCCUUUCUGCUUAUCAGCCAUGUCAUUUUCUUCCAUUUGUACAAAGCAGGCAAUACUGAGCAACUACCUUAUAGGAAUAACUGAGUUAAUAUCUAAGGGGCUUUCAGCAGUACCUGAAAUAUAGUAAGUGUUACAUAUAUGUUUACUCUUUUUAUUUUAUUUGGAAUUGUGAACUGAUAAUAAUUGAAGCCUACCUGCUAGUGGCCAUCUCUGCUGCCAGGUGAAAAGAGCCUGACUUAGAAUGAAGUCAGCGAAGGAAAGCAGAGUGGAGAGAAAAAGAGAGACUGAGUCCUGAUGACAUCAUUUAUUUACCUAGACCUAGCUGCUUGUGAAUAGAGCCCUACUGUGCUGAAUAGCUUCUGUCUGCUCUUUUCUAUUCUGCUCCCUGCUCUGUGAGGUAGGUUCCUUUGCUCUCUUGCUUUUGGUUGGGUUCAACAAAUGGGAAGCACCAGUGGGAGAUUAGAAGUUGAGAGGAAAAUGAAAUGAUGUUAUUUAUUUCCCUGGCUCCUUUCCUGCCAUGUCAUCAUCAGUUGGCUGUGUUCCUCUACUAAAUAGUACCUUAUCAGGAAUCCUAUCUCUUCUGUUCCCAAGCAGUUACCCCAGUUACCUCACUAGGUUUAGUUCCUGCUCCCUCCCUUUACCCCUUUUCACUUAGGGUUGGUAAUAGCUUACAGUUAUUACUAGCCCCAGUAUAGUUCACUACAACUUGUUGCUUUACCUAAACCCUGCUCAUACAUUUGUAAAUACUGUAGUUGUUUUAUUACACUCUUCUCAAAUGUCCCCACUUGAAAUAGCCUUCUAUUUCUUUUGGGGACUCUGAUAAAUUCACCUGUUUGGGUGAAAUAAUAGCACAUUUCCUGAAGUAUAUACAGUGGGACACAUGAUGUUUUAUGGGGGAAAGAGUUCUUGGUGAAAUUAGUUUGCUGUACAUUACGUUGUUUCCCUCCCAGGGAUUCAGAAGGCAAAACAUAUUAAAGGUUCUGAAAAGUCCUGAAAUAAACAUUUUGAACUUUAUUUAAGCUGAUAUAUCUUAAACUUACUUGAAUAUGUAGCACCUAUUAACAUGCCAUGGAAAUAGGACGUUUGGAGUAUUGUAAUUAAGAACAAUUCCUAUUAAUAUACAUGGGGCAACUGAGAAUUAAAGAGGUAAGUAAAUUAUUGAUAGAUCAUACACCUAGUUAGUAGCAGAGCCUGUUCUAGAAUCUGGAACUUCUGAUUUGGUUUGGUUCAGUAAGGUCACCAUUAUAUUAUGCUAUUCAUAAAAAGGAAUGUGGAUUAUAUAAGGCUUGAACAUUAUUAGUCUUACAGUCUUAGCCAAAUAAACUAACUGGCUUGCUUAUUUUAGCAGUUAUUCUACAAGAAUGGAAUUAAAAUAGAUUUUUUUUUUCAUGUUUAGAACUUGGCCCUGGGAAUAGAGGAAGGCUUGAAUUGAUUUAAGCAGGGCCAAAGUUGGAUUUCUCUAGGCUAAAUUUGGACUUCCCUGAGCCAAAAUCUAUUGCAUUUAACUGGCUUUACAAACCAACUAAACAUAACAGUUCAGAGGGAAAAGAAAAAAAAAAGCGAGAGACAGAGAACAAUUCUAUCACUCAUUUGCCUCCAUCUCUCAGCUGGCAUAAGAAAGAUGACCCACGUACUUCAUAAGAGCCUAAUUUACAGCUAAGGCCAGAUAAAAUCUCAGGUUCUUUUCAAAAGAAGUUAGUAAUACCUAUUAGAACAAUGAAUUGACUAUACUUGUCUUAGUUUUUUUUGUUUGUUUUUUGUUUUUUGUUUUUUUGGUGUGAUAGAUGUAACAGUGGCCCUAAUUCUUUAUCCUUGCUUGUAUUCAUGGUCAUUUUUCAGGUUCCUUUGAAGUACUCCCCCCACUGUGAUUCUGGGUCAUCUGCAUUCAGAGAUUUAGUGCAUUUUUACUUACACUUGUGCUUCUGCUGUUGACAUAAGAAUAUGCAUGGCUGAGUUAGCCUGCUGGAGCAUGAGACUCCAUGGAACAGAGCCAGGUUGCCCUGGUCACCCUCACUGAAUCUUGUCUAGAUUGGCUGAUGGCCAGCCAAACCCAAGAUAUGUGAAUGAUUCCAGCCAAGAUCAGCAGAGUCAUCUAACUGACACCUACCUGAUUCCAAACAUGUGAGCAAGGAAUGUCUAUUAUGCCACCAAUGUCUUAUAGCUAUUUAUUGUGGCUAUAGAUAUCUCAUCUUUGGAUGCAUUAUCAGAUCAUCUUCUUCAAGUACCUUAGAAGAUUCUCAGUCUCAUGUUUCUUGGGCUCUUGACCACUUGCUUUGCCUUAGCUACCACCUCAUAUAGUAACAGAUUACCAGCAGGUUUGUAUGAUUCCUCUGCUUGAGAUCAAUUAGCCAUAUGUUCAGAAUCCCUGGCCUAUAACAACACUUCUGUGCUUUAAAAACCCCAUGCCACAAUGACUGUUAAAAGGGCUAGGCGAUGUAGUCUGGUAGGUUUGUGAAGUUAACUGUCUGAAAAACUUGGAUCAAUGGACUAGAAAAAGCUGCUGGGUAAAUUGCUCUUCUUCUGAUGGACUGUAUAGAGACACUGUUUUUCAUCUUGCCUGUCCAGAAGCGUACUCUGUGGCCAAGCAAGUGUACUUGCCACAUGAUUGGCAGUGUCUCUUCAUGGCUUUUCAUGAAACAGCAGCAAGUGCUACACAGUAAUUUAUCAGUUUGCAUUUGCCUCCCAUUAUUGCCAGCCUCACUUCCUUUCUUCCUCGCUCUUACCAGCCUGGAUUGUACCUUUAAUAAAGUAGUGGAUAUAUUUCCUUUAGGGUCUCUUUUUCUAGGGAAGUCAGGUGUUUUAGUCUGGAUUUAGUUAGAAAAGCAGCAUCGUUACAAGUAUUACAUGAAUAAAGAAGUUUAGUAAAGAAAUUAAGGUUUACCCCAAUGUGAGAAUUACUGGGGUAAUAAAGGUCUGGAAGGCUGCAGCAGAAGAGAUUUAGAGAAGCAGUGACUAACUAGGUCAGCCGGAGAUUCUCAAAGUACUCAUGACUUCAUUUGUAGAAACAUGUAUAUCUUAAGCAUAUCAAGUGUCUCAUUCCUCUAAUCUUUCUAGGAGCCCUUUGGUUCAUCCUGAAGGUCCCCCUAAAUCCCUUCAGAAGUCUUAAAAAGGAGUAAAUGGCCACACCUUUUAUUUGUUCUUUUCUUUGAGGCCAUGUUAAUGGCAGUCCCUUGAUUUGGUCUUUGUACUAGGCUGUUUUUAAUGAUCACAUUUUAUUUGAUGAGAAACAAUUUUAUUUUCUAGUUCUGCAUAUCCUAGGUUAUGUAUUUCAUUUCAGUUCCAUUUCCAUACCCAUUGCCUUAAUUUUGAGCUUGUCUGUUUCUUACAUUUCUCAUUUUGACAGAAUAAGCUGACUGUUAUUAAGUACAAUAGAUAAGGUACCUAAGAGCCUCGAAACAUCACCAAAUACCAUGAAUGCAUUAGGUAUAUUUUUUGUCUUCCAUGUUACUGGAAGCAUUAAUUAUAGCAACUUUUUAUCUCCAAAUACUGACAAUUAAAAGACCCUAGUGAAAACUUUAACCAAACACUUACUGACCCUACAUUGAAGGCCACCAGCCAAAAAUCACCACCCAUACAUAAGAGCCAAACAUCACUAGACACUUGGUGAAAUCCUUCAAAUAUAAAAGGGGAAAAGGAGGGGAGAAAAUCCAAAGGAAAUAGACAAACGGAGAAUAAUGGCAACAAAAAAAAAACUGUCUUCAAAAUAAGAGUAUAUUAUAUUCACAAAACAAGAAUAGGAGAGUGUGAAAAAGAACAAGCAAUAAAAAAGAUCUCAGAAAUUUAAAAAGUGAUUGCUGAAAUAAAAAUUAAAUAUAAGAGUUGAAGAUAAAAUAUAGCAUAAGAAUAGAAAAUUCUGAAUUCCAAAUACCUAAGGCCAAUCUUAGUUAAAAGUUGUAAAUGCAACCAUAGGCUACAUGUUACAUUGUAUUUAAUUAAAAACCUUAAGAGGAAAGGCAAUAGAGCUUGUAACAGCUAUUACCCUUGGUUGUAAAGGAGAAGGUUGGAGAUUAUUUGUAUACCAACUACUUAAGUUUACAAAAAAUAAUGAGCAUUAGGUAGAUGGAAUGAAAGUCUAUUCAUACACUGUAUAUUAAGCUCUAUAUACACUGCAUAUCAUCAUCAUGACAUUGAGUUUCUAGCUGGAUUGCAGAGAUGAGCCAAAGCGCUUCUCCCCAAAUUAUUAUUUAUUCAUUUUUGAGACAGAGUCUCACUCUUGUCUCCCAGGCUGCAGUGCAGUGGUGCGAUCUCAGCUCACUACAACCUCCACCUCCCAAGUUCAAGCAAUUAUCAUGCCUUAGCCCCCCGAGUAGCUGGGAUCACAGGCAUGUGCCACCACACCCCGCUAAUUUUUGUAUUUUUAGUAGAGAUGGAGUUUUGUCAUGUUUGGCCAGCCUUAUCUGAAACUCCUGACCUCAAGUGAUCCUGCCUUUGCUUCCCAAAGUGCUGGGAUUAACAGGCCUGAGCCACAACACCCAGCCUAAAUUAUUUUUAAUUAUGACAUUUUUUGUAUUCCCUUGAGGCACUGACAACUAUAGUCUUAUUUUAUAUGUUAUAGUGAAUCAUAUUUAUCUCAUUAUAUAUUACAGAAUAUUUUGUUUGAUGGAGAAAAUUCACUGACCUGUGCUGUAAUGUUUAUACCAGCAAUUAGCUGAUUGAUUUACUAUGACCUCACUCUUUAUUCAGCAGUUCUGCCACUAUUACUAGCUAAUCCAACAACGAGGCCUUAUUUUGGCUUUCUUUCGAAAGGUCAUUUCUGACCCCAGCUUGAAGUUUGUUUAUUUUCACUUGAAGAGAUCUCUCAGAAAGUCAAAGAAAAUAGGAGGAAAAAAACUUAAGAUUAAGGGCCAAUCUAAGAGGUCCUUCAUUUGAAUAAUAGGAGUAACAGAAUGGGAAAGGCGUGGAAAAAAAUUUGUGAUUUCUAAAAUUGAGGACAUUAAGUCAUUAGAGUAAAAAAAAGAUGUACAUUAAGGCUUAUCAUCAAGGAAUUUCAGAACACUGUGGAUAGAAAAUACUAAAAGAUUUCAAACAGAAGAAAUAGGUCGUAUAUCGACCAAUAAUCAGGAUAUUAAAGGACUUCUUAACAACAUUGGAAACUAGAAGACAUGGGGUGAUGCCUUUAGAACUUUAAGUGAAAAUAGUUUUCUAUUUGGAUUCUAUUUUUAGUCAUGCAAUUAAUCAAGUAUGAAUAUAGUAUAAAGACACAGAAGGUCUCAAAGGUAUUACCUCCCAUAUAUUCUUGAGAUAAAGAUGCUUAGGAGAAUACUGAAGAUGUUUUCCAGUAAAACGGAGAAGGAAACCAAAAACCAAAAAAGAGAGCAUUAAGAAGUCAGCAGGCCAGGCGCGGUGGCUCACGCCUCUAAUCCCAGCACUUUAGGAGGCCAAGGCAGGUGGAUCGCCUGAGGUCUGGAGUUUAAGACCAGCCUGGCUAACAUGGCGAAACUCUGUCUCUACUAAAAAUACAAAAAUUAGUCGGGUGUGAUGGCAUGUGUCUGUAAUCCCAGCUACUCGGGAGGCUGAAGCAGGAGAAUCACUUAGAACCUGGGAGGCAGAAGUUGUAGUGAGCCGAGAUGGUGCCAUUGCACUCCAGCCUGGGUGACAGAGUGAGACUCCGUCUCAAAAAAAAUAAAUAAAAAAAUAAAAAGUCAGCAAAGGGAAGUUUCAGGGUUUCAGGAUUCAUUCAUCCAUUCUAAAAAAUUUUGAGUGCAUACUAUGUGUCAAAUUAUUGUCUAGGUGAUGGCUAUAGCAUGCCGAGGUAGUAAGUGCUAAGAAGAAAAUAAAGCAGAGUAAGGAACUGAUAGUGACUGGUGCAGGAAAGGGGUGCCAGUUUAAAUAGCAUGGUCAGAUGGAAAAGCCUGUGAUAAGGUAAAAUUGAGCAGAGACCUAAAUGAGAGAGAGUGAACCAUGCGAAUAAUUAAGUGAAUAAUGUUUUAAUUAUAGGGAACAAUAUGUGUGUGUCUAUAUAUAUAUAUACACACAAAGGUACUGAGGCAGCAGUAUACUUGGCAUGUUUGAGGAAUAACAAGGACACUAGUUUGGAACAGUGUGUGGGAGGGAAAAAAUGAUAGAAGAUGACAUCAUAGGGAGUAAUGGUGUGGAGCCAUGGUAAGAUGUUAAGAUUUUACUCUGAGUGAUGAGAUAGGAAGCCAUCAGAGAAUUUAAGCAAAUGAGUGACAGGAUCUGACUUAUAUUUUUAAAGGAUUAUUUGGCUUCUUUAUGAAAAAUAGACUGCAAGAGAGUAAGAAAUAAAAUAGGAAGAUCAAUUAGAAUGCUAUUUCAGUAGUCCAUUUGAGAGAUGAUAUUUGCCUGGACAAGGGUUGUGAUCAUGGGCGAGUGGUACAGAAUGACAAGAUCCUGCAUGUAUUUUUAAGGUAGAGCCAGUAUUUGCAGAUAGUUUAGACAUUGUGGUAGAUAUGAAAAUGUGCUGCCUAUAUCCCCCUUCUAGGAAGGACUUGCUAAUUAGCUGCAGGGAGUGUGAAGAACAGAAAUCCACCAGUAUCAGCACUUCAUCUGCAACAGCUAUAGAAAAAGCUUCACCUGAGGUUACCCUCGUCUUAGAUCUCAGGGCAGCCCUCAGUGGAGAUGUAAGGCCUUGCUACUUCAGCCUCAUUUAUUACACUGUCAGGCAAAACCUUCCUCAGAGCUCCCUCUAUUACAACUUAAUUUCUUCUUCUGCCCAAUCCUGCUUCCUCCCCUUCCCCUGAAAGGUGACACUUUCUAAUAAACAUCUUACACCCCAAACUCCAUCUCAGCAUUCCUCUUUAGAGGACUCGACCUGUGGUAAUUGUUAGUAGGAGUGAUCUGAGCUGCCAAUGAGAAUCCCAUCACAUGUGGCACAUGGAACAAAAGCCCAUGGCUCAAGGUGGUAACUUUUAUUAGUGGUAAAAUGAGAAGAUUUACCCACGGAAGAGAAUGUGCCAGCAAGUGCAGUAUAUCAGGUAUUUGAGACUCAUGAAGGAAAUAGUAAAUUUAAGAAUAACAGAAUUGAAUGGCCAAGUGCCACUAAUGCUCUGUAGAAAGAGGGCUUCUUUGGUUGCAUACAAAUCUCAUCUAGAAUUUAAUAGUCCAAGUAGCCAAACUGGUAUUUGUCCUUAAGAAUAAAUACUGGAAGAUCAAGCACAGAAAGUCUAGAAUAGAGGCAUGUGAAUGGACAUACUUGUGUCAAGUAUGUACAUGAACUGUGAAGGUCUCUGUAUUACGUGCAGUGCCCACCAGAGAGCAUUCAGUACUGAAGAGUCUCUAAACAAUAAAGCAAACUAAACACAUUGCCUAGUUGACGUCAUCCUUCCUGCUUCAGUUAUUCGCCACCCAGUGCUAGCACAGUGGGCACAUGAAUGGAAUGUCCACUGUGGAAAGGAUGAAGACUAAGCAUAGGGUUCAGUAGCUUGAGUUUCAACUUACCAAGGCUGCCUUAGCUGCUGCUGCUGUUGAAUGUCCAACCUACAAGCAACACAGACAAUACUGCACCCCUGAUAUAAUACCAUUCUUCAAUAUCAAGUUGGUUACAUUGGGCCCCUUCCACACUGGAAGGACCAGCAUUUCCUUGUCAUAGAAAUAGACACAAUUUCCAGAUAGGAGUUUGCUUUUCCUCUUUGCAGAGCCUCAGUCAGUAUCACCAUUUGAGUUUACUUAGUAUUGUAUUGACCAGCAUGCGAUCUCACAUUAUAUCAUAUCAGAUCCGGAAACCUAUUUUAUGGAAAACCAAGCGCAGGAGUGGACCCAUAUCCACAGGAUCCACUAAUAAUAUCACUUUUUUCACCACUUGGAAUUUGUCAGCUUGAUAGAACAUUGGAACAACCUGCUGAAGGUACAGCUGAACACCAGCUCAUAGGCAAAUUCUACAAGGAUAGGAUGCCAUACUCCAAGAUACAGAGUAUGUACUGGAUCAAUUAUCCUUAUAUAGCAUGUGCCCCAAUAUGAAGAAUAAAUGGGUCUUGGAACCCAUUUAUUCCUAGGGGUAGAUGCAAAGAGAGUAGAAGAAGAGGUGCCUCCCCUCCGUGCCAUCACUUUUAAUGACCCAUAUGGUACUUUGCACCUCUUCAUAACUCUGAACUCUGCAGUGAGAGGUCUUGGUCCCACAAGGGGACACAGUUUUGCUGAGAGAUAUAUAAAAAAUCUCACUGAAAAACAUAAGCUGCAGCAGCUACCUGGAUACUUUCGGUUCCUUGUGUCUGUCUAGGGAGCAGCAGCCAAUAAAAGGAGUCAAGAUCAGUUGACCCUAAUCAAGAGGAGAUUGGAAUCCUGGUUACACAAUCUGGGCAGAAGUAAUAAAUGUGGUGCCCAAGUGAUAAACCUACCAAAUUGAGACUAAUGUGUAGGUGUGGCAACCCAUCCUCAAAAGGGCAUGAUGGCCUGGAACUCAGGCCUCUCAAGGAAUGUGGGUCUGAAUUAUACCAGAUAAACCACCAGGAGCAGCAGAGGUGGUAGCAGAGGCUGAGGGAAAUCUAGAAUUGAUAGUGGAGGAUGAGGGGAUGUGACAAGUAUUGAUGGCAUUCCCAAGCCCCACUGCAGCAGCAAGCACUGUAAUUUGUCCCACUAAUCUCCCAUCUUCUAAAUUUCUGAGAGGUCAAGAAAAGAGGUCUCUUGAUUCCUUUAGGAACUGCUCCCUAAGCAUACAGGGAGACAUAGAUCUAUGUGGAGCAAAGGGUGGAUUGUAAUAAGCAAAGAGAUACACUGCCUGAUUCACUUUAAGAAAGGACUGACCUCCCAGUUGCAAGGAAUGAGGUCAGCAGCCUCCAACUGUCAGCUCCUUCAGAGUCUGCUUCAACUGCAGAAGGACACUGUGCUUGAGGUCAUACCCUUCCCAUGUCUGGUGACUGAAGUCCAGCUGAAUGUAGCUGCCAAAGUUACCUUAAUGCCCAUGGGAAGCAAAAAAUCAAAGAGUUUAAACAGAAUUUUGAGAAAUCCCAAAUCAGUUUUUUUUCAGCAUAUGACAUUUUGGAGUAGUUUGUUAUUCAGCAAUAGAUAACAGAAAUUGGUAUCAGGAGUGGGGUGUUACCAUAACAAAAGGUUAAACCUUACAUGGUAAAAAGGACUUUGCCUCUGUCAUUAAGUUAAGCACUUUGAAAUGUAGAGAUUAUCCUGAAUUAUCUAGGUAGGCUCAAUAUAAGCAUGAGUCCUUAAAAGUGGAAGACGGAUACAUGAGAGGAUGUCAGAAUGAUGUGAAAUGAGAAGAACUCAACCUGCUAUUGUUGGCUUUACAGGUGAGUGAUAGGAACCACAAGCCCCAAGCAGCCUCUGGAAGCUGGAAAAAGCAAAGAAACAGAUUCUUUCCAGAGUGUCCAGAAAGGAAUGCAGUUCAGCUAACAUCUUGAUUUUAGAUCAGUGAGAUUUUUGUGUUGGACUUCUACAGAACUAUAUAAGAAUAAAUUGUGUUGCUUAAGCACACUAUAAUACAUGUGGCAAGAAGCUGCCAGCUAAGCCUUGAAGAAUAGUGAACAAACUCUUACUGGAGGAUGGGAAGGCAGUAAAUAAAUUAUUGAAUUAUUGAAAUAAAUGGAGGAUUGAGUUAUGCAUUGACAGAAUGCUUAGCAAUAAUUUUGCUUGUCUUAAUGUGGAACAGAAAAUGAAACUUAAUAGCUUGUAGAUGUCUUAAGGAGAUUUCCAGGUGAAUGUUGAAAGUACUGAUGAACUUAUUAUGGCUGCAUCUCAUAAUGUACAGGAAGACAUUUACUGAGUGAACUAAAGAAGGAACUGUUCAAUUUGAAAGCAGAAUUUAGAGGAAAUUUUUCAACCUAGUACUUGUCAUUUUUUUAUAGAAAAGGAAAAAUAGAUGGAAGAUGGAGCCAAAAUCCCAGAGGGAGGAGCCAAGAAGCAAGGAGAGCAAUGGAUUAGGAAACCACUACCAGAGGGAUGAACUGAACCACAAUCAAGGAAUAGCCUCUUCCUUUGGUGUAGGGGGACCCUGAAAACAAUUUAAUUUUAUGCUUCCUGUUUCCUUGUCUCCUUUUUUGAAUGAUAGUCUCUGUGUGGUGUUCCUAUCCUAGAAAACCUUAACUGGGACAAGCUACUCUCAAGCAUCUUCACUUGAGAAACAGUAACUGAGGAAGUUUAUUGUAUCUGGACAUGGUUUAGAUGAUAAGAUUCUGAACUUAAACUUAUGCCAUAAUGGAGUGAGACUCUUAGGGUACAGAGUAAGUACAUUUUUGCAUGUUAGUGAGACAAGAACUGUGGCCGGGGGCAGACUGUGAUAGUUUUUGAAGAUGUCCCUCAAACAAUUCCUUCCCUUCCUUGGACUCCUCUCUUCAGAGGGUAGAGUCCAUUUCCUUUUCCUUUUAAUCUGGAUUGGCCUUCUAACUCACUUUGACCAAUAAAAUGUGGUAAAAGUAAGGUCUGGCAGUUUUCACUUUCACUCUCCUGAACCUUCAUAUUAGAAUUCCAGGAUAUCCUUCUAGAGAUAUCCAUAUCUCUAGGGACAUGGUGAGUCCCUAGAGACACCACAUGGAAAGGCCACCUAGGGAAGAACUGAGAUGCCCCAGUCAAUAGCACUGCCUUAGUCAGUUUGGGCUAGUAUAACAGAAAUAUCAUAGAUUGAGUGACUUUUUUUCUUUAAAAAAAUGAGAUUGUGGAACCUGAAAAUACAGUGUAGUAAGAGUGGAGAGAAAGGCCACCUAAGGAAGAACUGAGACGUCCCAGUCAAUAGCACUGCCUUAGUCAGUUGGAGCUACUGUAACAAAAAAUAUCAUAGAUUGAGUGACUUAAACAACAGAAAUUUAUAUCUUACAUUUCUGGAGACUGAAAAUAUGGAAAUCCAAGAUCAGAGUUUCAGCAUGGUUAGGUGUUUAGUGGGCGCUCCCUUCCUGGUUUGCAGACAGCCAUCUUCCUGCUAUAUCCUCACAUGAUGCAGAGAGAGAGAACUCUGGUAUCUUUGUCCCCUUAUAAGGGCACCAAUCUCAUCAUGGAGGGUCUUCAACCUCAUGGCUUCUUGGAACCAAAUUACUUCCCAAAGUCCUCACCUCCAAAUCUAGCACAUUGAGGUUUAGGGCUUCAACAUAUGAAUUUCAGUGCAUAGAAAGCACCAAGUCCUCAGACAAAGAGAACUUGAACCUUCUAACUCAGCUUAGCCAUUAUCUGCAUGCAACCACAUAAGUGACCCUGGGUAACACCAUCUGGAGCUGAAGAACCACCAGCCAGUACACAGAAAUGAGAAAUUUUAAAAUGGUUGAUUUAGGUAAUUAAGUUUUGGGGUGGUUUAUUACAUAGCAAUUGAUAACUGAUACAACAGUCUUUUCGUUAGUAGAAGAGGGGGUAAGAAAGAAAGACUUAUGAAGAAAAGACCUGUAGAAAAUCGGGCCUACGUACCUCUAUUUUUUUUUCAUACUCCCGUGUUUUUUUUAGUCCAUGCUGGUGGUAUCCUCAUCAAUGCAAUUUUCUUUAAAACUCUGUGAGCCUUUAUAUCAGAUUAGUCCACCCCAUUAGAACAAAAGCAACUUCUAUAAAUAUUGAGACAUUCCCUUUCUACCUUUGGCUAAGAAUUGGGGUGCUAUAGAUAAUUCCCAAAAGAUUAUCUAGCCUACAGGGCCGAUGAGGUAUAGCUUGAAGUCAUUCUAAAGUCUUCACAAAGGAUCUUACAGCCUUUGAUUUUAUUAUCACUCUGGGACCACGUUUUACUGUUGGCACGUUCGGCUUUUCUCAUCUUUUCCCUGAGAUCAUUUAUGAUGUGGAAAUUACUUUGCUGGCUGAAGUUGGGAAUAGAAAACAGUAGAGAAUACUUCAAGAGUAUUCUAGGUAUGCACUAAGUUUAUGGGAAGAUAUGCCAUCUACAUAAUUUACCUUCCUCUCUAGGCCCAUCAUAAAAAUCUUUGAAAAAUUAAUACUACAUUUUAGUAUGAAUAUAAGUUAAACUUAGAGGUGAUAUCUAUUUUGUGGUUAAAUGUGUUAUAAACAUUUAUUUAGUGAAAUACAGUACAAUUACAACAAGCAUCAAUGAAUAUUUAAUGAGCAGCUGUUAAUUUCUGAAGCAGAAAGAAAGAUGAAUAAAAGUUCUGGUUUUACUUUUAAAAGUGAAGGCUAACUGUUAGCUCAAGAAAUACUUUAUGUUUGUCCUAUAUGAAAGUGUUGAUUGCACCUGGUUCUUUGCUGUAAAUUAAAUAAAAAUUCAAAUAUUUGUAAAA